GCUGUAGUGGCUUCGUCUUCGGUUUUUCUCUUCCUUCGCUAACGCCUCCCGGCUCUCGUCAGCCUCCCGCCGGCCGUCUCCUUAACACCGAACACCAUGCCUUCAAUUAAGUUGCAGAGUUCUGAUGGAGAGAUAUUUGAAGUUGAUGUGGAAAUUGCCAAACAAUCUGUGACUAUUAAGACCAUGUUGGAAGAUUUGGGAAUGGAUGAUGAAGGAGAUGAUGACCCAGUUCCUCUACCAAAUGUGAAUGCAGCAAUAUUAAAAAAGGUCAUUCAGUGGUGCACCCACCACAAGGAUGACCCUCCUCCUCCUGAAGAUGAUGAGAACAAAGAAAAGCGAACAGAUGAUAUCCCUGUUUGGGACCAAGAAUUCCUGAAAGUUGACCAAGGAACACUUUUUGAACUCAUUCUGGCUGCAAACUACUUAGACAUCAAAGGUUUGCUUGAUGUUACAUGCAAGACUGUUGCCAAUAUGAUCAAGGGGAAAACUCCUGAGGAGAUUCGCAAGACCUUCAAUAUCAAAAAUGACUUUACUGAAGAGGAGGAAGCCCAGGUACGCAAAGAGAACCAGUGGUGUGAAGAGAAGUGAAAUGUUGUGCCUGACACUGUAACACUGUAAGGAUUGUUCCAAAUACUAGUUGCACUGCUCUGUUUAUAAUUGUUAAUAUUAGACAAACAGUAGACAAAUGCAGCAGCAAGUCAAUUGUAUUAGCAGAAUAUUGUCCUCAUUGCAUGUGUAGUUUGAGCACAGAUCCCAAACCUUACGGCCAAGUUUCUUCUAGUAUGAUGGAAAGUUUCUUUUUUCUUUGCUCUGAAUAAAACUGAACUGUGGGUUCUCUAUAAGUGGCAUUUUGGGCUUUCCCUCUUUUUUGUAAAGCAAUGUCUGCCUAGUUUAUUGUCCAGUUAACUUUAGUGACCUUUUAAAAGUUGGCAUUGUAAAUAAAACAACUUGCAAAAAAGUUUUCUGGAAUAGAAUUAACAAAAUAUUAUCUUUAUUCAUGAGUUGGAAACUGGAAAAAGGCUUCUUGAAGUAAAUGUUCUGAGUGGAGCUACUAGGAUGUCUUCCAGCCUCCUGCAGUCAAGGAGUACCACUGUAUUGAUUAGCCUGUAUGUAGCAGGGCUCCCUUCAUUGCAUCUGAGGACUUGUUUUCUUUUUCUUUAUUUUUAAUCCUCUUAGUUUUAAAUAUAUUGCCUAGAGACUCAGUUACUACCCAGUUUGUGGUUUUUUGGGAGAAAUGUAACUGGACAGUUAGCUUUUCAAUUAAAAAGACACUUAACCCAUGUGGGAUGUCAUCUUUUUAUAAUUAGUGUUCCCAUGUGGAGAAAAUUAUUCACACUACUUGCAUGUAAAGAAUAAUUUAACUUUUAACAUUAAAAUAUGUGGUAAAACCCAGAAAGCAUCCAUCAUGAAUGCAAGAUACUUUCAAUAAAAAGUAAGUUAUAUAGUAGGUAGUUAAGUUUGCUUUUGUGGACUUAAAUGUGUCUCUUCACUUAAAUGGGUUGAAUGUGUAUAUAUUUGUUCAGCUUGAAAAGACUUAGUUUAUAUCCUAGCUCACUGGAGGCUGCUGACAUAACCAUAACUUCUGUCCCUUCUAAUUGUCAUUUAUAUGCCUAACUGGAGCUAGUACUUUAAUUCUUAACACAAAAUUACUCUGCCAUUGUUUCCAGCUUCCCUCCUACAAUAGAAUGAAGUUUUUUUGAUGGCUUGAGAUGGCUCACAAAUUUUGAUUUUUUUUUCUUCCUUGUGCUCCCUUUUUUUCUCCUUGCUUUUCCAGUUAACAUCUAUAUUCACAUGUAAUCUUGUUUUCUCUUCACAUUCACUGAGUUGUUCAGGCUCAGAUCAUCCCUUGACAGUAGUUUGCCUUCAUCUCACCUUUCAUUUGUCCCAAAUUCACCUUAUUUAAUAAAGUCCCAUAUGUUGUCUCACUUAAUUCCAAUUUGUUGUCUGUACCAGAGAUAGGAAACUAUAAUGUGUGGGUCAAAUCAGGCCCAUAGCCUGUUUUUGUAGUCUUUGAGCUAAAAAUGGUUUUUACGUUGUAAAGAGUUAUUUAAAAUUCUCUCUCUCUCUCUCUCUCUCUCUCAGGAGAUAAGCUUGUUUUCUGUUUGUCCUGGUUUUAGUGGGGAAGGUAGCGGUGUAUAGUCCUAGCUGAAUUGUCUCAUCUACCAAUUCCUGCUAUUAUAAGAUCAACUUCUGCAAAAACCUUAUCCACCUCAAGUAUCCUUAGCAGCUGGGCAUGGUGGCUUAUGCCUGUAAUCUCAACAUUUUGGGAGGACAAGACAGGAGGAUCGUUUGAGCCCAGGAGUUCAAGACCAGCCUGGGCAACACAGAAAGUCCCUGUCUCUCCAAAAAAAAAAAAAAAAAUUAGCAGUCAUAUGGUGCAUGCCUAUAAUCCCAACUACUUGAGAGGCUGAGGUGGGAAGAUGGCUUGAGCCUGAGAGGUCGAGGCUGCAGUGAGCUGGCAUUGCACCACUGCACUCCAGUCUAGGCAAUAGAGCGAGACCUUGUCUCAAAAACAAACCAGAAGUAUCCUUAGCAGUAUUAUGACAAACAAAUCUUCACUGAAGGUCCAGGAUUACUGCCAUAUGCCAUGUUUAACUUGUAAAGGAAGUAUCACCUUCUAAGAAACUGGAGCUUGUUAUUACCACUUGAUCUGUAUAAUACUCAGCAGUAGUUAGAAUUAUAUGAGUAAAUAACGUCACUAUCCGUAUUUAAAGGAUAAUGAGAUCUUUCAGAAAGAUUGGAUGGACAGACAAUAUAGUAGUAAUUUAAAUUUUUGUUUCCUGACUUUCUGUAGUCCCUAAACAAACAACAAAAAAUCCUAGUAAUCUUAAACUUUUACAUUAAUAGAGAUCCAAGAGAAAAUAAGCCAUUUUUCACCAUUGUGGACCCAAAUAAAUCAUAGACAUGGUAUUAAGAAGCCCUUUUCAGUCUGGUUGCAGUAUUAUUUUCCUACCUUUCUUUUUCCUGUUCCCUGCUGUAUGCCCACUAUUCCUUUAAUAUAUCUACUAGAACUUUUCUAGGCUUUCACCUGGAGUGAGUGGUCCUUUCUCAUUAUCACAGUAGCCAAACCUCAGUCUUCAAAACUCCACUCAUUUCUGGCUACUCUCUUACUUCCCAACUAUUCUUCUAAACUAAUAUUGUGGCAUUAAGUCAUACCUUGAGGCUGGAGUUUUAGUGUCUUCAUGGCCUUGGGCAAGUUGGAAAUAGGUACUACGGUUUUAUAGAUCUAGUGCAGUCUGCUUUAUAUUAGUUCCAGAACUUCAUUGGAAGUCACUUGACAGCAGGAUUUAACUUGUAUUUAGCAGCACUACUCCAUGAAUUUCAGUAUAAGUAACAGAAGUGAAAAGUCCUUGUGAAAUGCAGGUACAGGGCAUAAUGAAAACAAGAAGAGUAGUUUUAAUGCAUGAGAGGGGAGAGCUUGAUAAUAGCUGAUAAUAGCCUUGGUUUGGAGAGUGGUUACUGAUGAAUUAUGAAGACUUUCUCUAAUUACUGUUAUAGUAGUAAAGGAAAGAAAACCCUUGUUGAUAAAGUAAACUUAGGGAUUAAUUAGGAAAUGCCUUUUAUUUCACCAGGAAAGAGAAUGAGAGGAAGAAGGUAUUUGGCAGAUUUGGGUGAUUGAAGGAUGUUUGUCGGUUUCCUCUGUAAACAACAUGCUGCUUUCUGCAGUGUGCUGCUUUUAAUGAUGAAGUCCUUUCAAGGACUCCAUGGCAGUCCUUUGGCUUCUCACCUUUUCAUUGAUUAUGUCACUUGUGAUCUAAAAGUAAACCAAAACCUUCCUGAAUGUUAGCUUAUUAUUUUCUCCUUAACAUUGUCAUAGGCUAAAGAUGUGCCCCCUCAAAUUCUAAUAAUUUUUUUUUUUUUUUUUUUUUUUUUGAGACAGAGUCUCACUCUGUCGCCCAGACUGGAAUGCAGUGGUGCGAUCUCAGCUCACUGCAACCUCCGCCUCCUGGGUUCAAGUGAUUCUCCUGCCUCAGCCUCCCGAGUAGCUGGGAUUACAGGCACAUGCCACCAUGCCUGGCUAAUUUUUUUGUGUUUUUAUUAGAGAUGGAGUUUUACCAUAUUGGCCAGGCUGGUCUUGAACUCCUGACCUUGUGAUCCGCCCGCCUUAGCCUCCGAAAGUGCUGAGGUUACACGUGUGACCCACCGCACACGGCCCUAAUAAUUCUUAAGUUGUAGAAGCAAGUUACUCUUUUGAAGUGCCAUGUGUUAGCUUGCCUUAAUCUAUUCUUGGUAUACAAAAUAGAUACUGCUUUACAGUUCUUAUAUUUUCUCAGAGAUUCACAAAAUCAUCCUGUAGCUCCCUGUGUGGGAUUAUAGCUGUGACUUUUUACUCUACAACUGUCAGAAUACACCAGCUCCUGGAAUUAAGCAAGAACUAUAUUGUGACUUGGUUGGACAGGUAACUGCAGCCUUGUAACAUGACAUCAUAGUAAUGCUGAGCUUAUCUUAAAACUAGCUGGGGAGGGAGGAUAGUAACAGUGAGUCACUGUGGGCAUCUCACUUAGGGCAGGCAGAUAUUCCAAAUCACAUUGAUUUUUCAGUUUACGUAAAAAUUGACCAAUCCUAUGGGCUGUGUUCUGAUCCCAACAUAAAUUUUGUUUAAGUUAAUUUGCCUAGGCUCUCAAUAAGGCAGUUUGGGAAUAUAAGGUGAUUUUCCACCAGAAAAGAGAAAAUUGAGAGAGCAGCAGACCUCUUGCUCUCAGCACCCUUUACAAGCUUAACUUUUGCUUGCCACCAUUAGCUUUUGAAGAUUUUUUUUAACUGCUCCUUGCAGAGCAGGACUACCCCAUAGGCAGUGUGCCCAGAGUAGCCCGAAGAGCUUUUUGAUUCUUCUUUUAAGAGACAAGGUCUCACCUCUGCCCCCCAGGCUGGAGUGCAGUGAUGUGAUCACAGCUCAUUGCAGCCUCGAACUCUUGGGCUCCAACAGUCCUCCUGCCUCAGCCUCCUGAAUAGCUAGGACUACAUGUGUGUGCUACCAUGCCUUGCUAGUUUUUGUUUUUUUAAAUUGAUUUUUAUAGAGAUGAGGUCUCCUCAUGUUGCCCAGGCUGUUUUCGAAUUCCUGGGCUCAAGAUCCUCCUGCCUCAACCUCCCAAAGUGCUGGUAUUACAGAUGUGAGCCACAGCACCCACCAAUUUUUCCUUUUCUAAAGCUCAGUGUACAUUCUGGUAGGAAGGAAUCAACCAAGUAAAUGUUCUCCCUACAAAGUUGUUUGAGGAUUUGAAAAGUUAAUCUUCAAUUAUCUGGAUUUGAAACCAGUCUAUAACUUUUUAAGCUAGGAAGAAGUCAAGAAUAAGAAGAUUGCAAGCAAAGGGAAAGCUUACAAAAUGGCUGAAUCCUUAAAGUGUAGCUCCUGGCUUCUCCUUGGUAGGAAGCAUUAGACAUGGUUUCCCUCUAGGGAGCUGGGAGCUUUUGGUGUAGUUCAGGAGAGAAGGCAUAAAUACUGCUGGGAGGGAGUGGAUAACUCUAAUAAAAAUGUUCCUGGGCUGGGCACGGUGGCUCACGCCUGUAAUCCCAACAUUUUCAGAGGCUGAGGUGUGCAGAUCACGAGGUCAAGAGAUCGAGACCAUCCUGGCCAACAUGGUGAAACCUCAUCUCUACUAAAAAUACAAAAAUUAGCUGGGCGUGGUGGCACAUGCCUGUAGUCCCAGCAACUCGGGAGGCUGAGGCAGGAGAACCGCUUGAACCCGGGAGGCGGAAGUUGCAGUGAGCCGACAUCACGCCACUGACUGCAGUCCAGCCUGGCGACAGAGCGAGACUCCGUUUCAAAAAAAAAAAGUUUCUGGACAGAACAGAUUAAUGAGCCAAUGGGGGGCUACAGAGCUGAAAGGUGCUACGAAAGGUUUUGUAAAGUGAAACUAAUUUGGUUUCAAGAAUCAAGUUGGAUUUGUUUGGGGGUGGACAGAUGCCAAAGUGAGGAAAAAGCAGUGCACAGUCAGGAACUAACAGCAGAAGGUUGGGUGUUGGUACAUUUCCCUGAGAAUAUAGACUAAAGAGAAAUUAGGGCAGGAUUAGUCACAGUACUUUGCUGACACUCAGUAGUAUUUUAUCAGCAUUUAUUCAUCAGACCCACAUUAGGCAGGGCAAUUUUUGAGUGAGCUAAAUUCUAAUUUUUUUAAUUUUAAUUUUUAUUUAUUUAUUUUUUGGCUGUUCAACUAAACCAGUCUUUUGAAUGUUGGGGGUUUUACAGUUAGAGUCCUGAUGACUUUUUCUUGUUUACUGUUGUUAAAAAUCACUACCUCCAGUGGUCACAGAGAAUGAGUAAGAGAACUGGCUGUGCAUAUCAAGAUGAAGUAUGGUGUAAGAAAUAUUUCAGAGCAUGUCCUUUGGCCCAAGAUUGAGCCAUUUGGACACCUAAGCAGGAUUGGCUGAAUGUUAUCCUUUCUGCUGAGGCAUCAGUGGAGAUGAUCAUUAGUGGUGGCCGAAAAGUGUUGUCGAAGGUGCUCUUGCUUGACACACUUCCAAUGCGGGACAUAGUUUGAGUGAUAGAUGGCUAAUUCAUUGAUAAUGUACUUGUUGCCUUGCAGUCUUGUGUACUGCUGGCUACCUCUGGUCUGUGUGCCAGUAUUGAGCAGCAUUCUAUGGGAGGAAUGUAGUUGCUCAUAACAGUGUCUGCUUCCACAUCUGUAGUUCUUGCGACCUUCUGAUAUCUGUCAACUUUAAAUUUUCUGGAAGUAUUUAAGUAUAUUCAGACCUUCUGAUAUCUCUUAACUUCAAAUUUUCAACCUGCUAUAUAGCAGCCUCUUAUUGCACACUGAGGAUCAGCUUAUUUCCUUAAAGUGCUCUCACUUUGAAUACCUCCCACCUAUCUGGUGAAAAUUCUUAUUUGUCCUUUCUUUCCUGAAUGUACCAUUUCACAACCUCUAACUGCCUUCUUCAGUUGCUUUGCAGAUUUUUCUGUUCCAGGAAGCUUACGGAAAGGGGUGGGAAAAUAGAGAAGCUGUACUCUAUCCUCAAGUACUCAAGCAGGGUUUCCAGAGUGGCUUUGUAAAAAUUUUUAUUUAUUUAUUUAUUUAUUUUUGGUGAGUGGAACCUGGCUUUUCCUCUUCCCUCCCCAAGCCCCACCCCGCUUCCUGACAUUGCACAUGCCUGAAAGAACUAGGCUUCAGAUAAAAGAAUGAGAACACUUGAAUGAAAAAGGAAGACUUGGUCCAGAGCCCCUGGUGAAUAUGAAAGAAGUAUUGGCCUGGACUAUCUCCCGCAUAAUUCACAGCUGCUAUCUUGUCUUCAGAAGUGAAACAUCCCUUACCAAUAGUGACCUAACUUGUGAGGACUGCUUGUGAUAGUAUAGUUCCCACCCCCAGGACAUAAGUUUUCCCUUUCCAGUUAACAUGCCUAAUCCCAUGCUAUCUUUAAGAGCUUGAAAAUCCUUCCUGACCUGAGCUAGGCUUUUAUUCUAAGGGACUGUGUAUGUGAACAUCCCCACCAUCUAUGUUUCCUGUUUUCAAACUCGGUGCCGUUUUGAGUAUUUUCAGAUGCUCACUGCCAGUAAUGGUUUGUUAGUAGCUCCAAACUAUUAGAGAAGAGCUCAGGAGUCAGAAUUUGAAAGAUGCCCAUAGGGUGAUUUGAGAUUUGGAACAAGGUUAUCACAAUAAGUUGGGAUUGGGGGAGUUGACACAACCAGGGUCUGCUUGGGUGGGCAGCUGUUUCAGAAACCCUUGGUGAACUCUUAAAGCCCUGAAGAGCUUAAAAAAUGCUCUGAAGAGAUCUGAGAGUCGCAGUUAAGGACUCUCAAAGAACCUCAAAGAAAAGCCAACUUAGCCUUUUUAUACAAUUAACUAGAUUUGGGUCUUAAAUUCUACUUUGACAUAUAGGCCUAAGAGGUAGUUUAACAUGGCCUUGUUACCCUUACCCCUUCUGUUCUGUGCUGUUUUCUGAGAAACGGAUGCAGGAACUGAUUCCCUUUCUUCCUCUCUGGAACAGGAUAUAAAGAACCCUUCCGCUUCCCUUUACUUGUGGCCUUCCUGGCCAGGCUUAUGUAUACUGAACAAAGCUAGGGUGCAGUGCUUCUGAGCUAGCUGUUAGGGGUCCACAGCCAGAAGGAAUGGGAGACCACAGGAGCCAUUCAAAAGAUAAUUACAUGUCAGAAGAGAGUCCAUCCAUGGGGUUCUGUUAAAGUAGACACCUUCACGUUGGGAGACAUAGGCUUUGUCUGCUUGCUGGGCUGAACCCUCACCAUAUCCACAGAGAACAAAAUGGGGAGCAGCUGUACCAGGGGAGGGAUGAACGUCUUUCACCCAAGUUGCCAGUCUGCUAGUUGUCUGGAAAUGUUCAAGGGAGGCUAAGGUAUCUUGUCUUAUGAUGUCUCAGGAAACAGGGUUGGUUCUCAGCUGGCAGUGAAGGGGGACUGGUGUGGUAUUAGCAGUUGAACUUGAGGUUGCAAUCUCAAGUCACCCUCUGGCCUCGCAGGAAUGCACCAGGGUGAUUUGGGAGGAUCUGAGUUUCCUUUAUGAAGUCAGAUUAAAAAAAAAAAAAGCUGAUCUGAUUUAAACAGAGUUGCCAAAGACUUCCCCGCCAAUACACAAAGACUGCAUUGUUCAGGUACCCUGUGUACUCUAAGUGAGACACCAAAUCAGAUGCAGCAACCUGGUCUUGCAUAAGCCCUGGUUAGAAUGUAGGUUUUUUAAACAACUAGGCCAGUAGCCAGAACAGAAUUCUUUAAAAUGGGACAGAUGUCCAGAGAAUGGCUAGUGUCCUCUAGCACUCUCUCAGAAGCAAAAGCAAGUCUGGGGUUACAACUUCCAGUGGCCUACUUUAAAUAGACGCUGUUCUGGAAAAUGACUUUAUACUUUAAACACAAAAUCCAAAAAAUAGAACUCAGUGGAGUGACAAUGACAAUGCAUGAUGGUGGCCCAGUGGCUGUCCCAUGUGAAAUACUUCUUGCCUGACAUGUAUCAUCUACUUGUUGACUGACCUAUUGAGGUGCCUUCAUGACACCUUUUACAUUCAUGAUAGGUCUCAGGAAGACAGCAGUGUACUUGGUGGAAACUCAUGUAAAAAGUGGGUUGUAGGGAGCUAAACAGUGAGUACACAUGGUAUAUGGAUACGGAAUGGAAUAAUAGACAUUGGAGACUUCAAAAGGUGGGAGAUGAAAGGGGGAUGAGGUAUGAAAUCCUACCUGUUGAGUACAAUGUACACUACUUACGUGCACAGUACACUGUUUGGGUGAGAGGCACACUAAAAGCCCGGACCUCACCGCUACCCAGUAUGUUCAUGUAACACAGCUGCACUUGUACCCCCUAAAUGUAUACAAAUAAUCUAAAAAUAGCCCGGACCUCACCGCUACACAAUAUAUUCAUGUAACACAGCUGCAUUUGUACCCCCUAAAUGUAUACAAAUAAUCUAAAAAUAAAGUGGAUAUGGUGGCUGUCGUGUCCACCAACAGCGUA